ACAGACCCAGCCGCCCCGGCUCCCCCGCCGUCCGCGUCUGCGCCGGCCCCGGGGCCUGGUCGGCGGCGGCGGGGCCGGUCGAUGGCCCGGGCGGCGGCGGCGGCAUGCGGCUCCUGUUCCUGGCGGUGCUGCGGCCACACACCGGCAACGCGGUCACGGCCCAGCGCGUUCGGGCCCAUCUAGAGGCUGCAGGGCACGUGUGCGUUUUGAAGGAUGCCUUUGACUUUGAAAGCCGAUCUGAGAUUGCAAACCUCAUCUUGGCUGAGAACUGCGAGGCUGCCCUGGCUCUUCAUCUCUAUAGGGGAGGCAGGCUUUUGCAAGGCCACCGAAUCCCUUUUGGAGUCAUCUUUGGUGGAACUGAUGUAAAUGAAGAUGCCAACCAGGCGGAAAAAAACACAGUCAUGGGCAGAGUUCUUGAGGAAGCCAGAUUUGCUGUCGCUUUCACAGAGUCAAUGAAGGAAAUGGCACAAGCGCAGUGGAAAGCAAGACAGAUCUCAUUGGCUGUCACAAGUGCAGUUCCUGUACAGCCGCAUGCUAAGGGUAAGGUCUAUGUCCAGAGUCAAGGAAUUGCAACAACACCAAACGCCGCUUUUAACUGGAAUACCUUUCUUCAACGCUCUGAGAUUAACCAAAGUGCUGAUAAUUUGCACAUAUUUCUUCUGAUAUGUGGACUUCGACAAGUUAAGGAUCCUCUCUAUCUGGUGGACGCAUUUUCAGCCUGGCAUCAGGAGGAGCCCAAUGUGCACCUGGUGAUUGUGGGUCCUGAAGUCGAUCCAGUGUUUACAAGGGAAGUGAAAGCCAAAGUGAAAAGAGCCGCUGGGGUACGAUUGAUUGGAGAGAUGCCUCAAGAAGAUCUGCACGCGGUGGUGAAGAAUUGCUUCGCGGUGGUGAAUAGCUCUGUCUCUGAAGGCAUGUCAGCUGCAAUUUUGGAGGCAAUGGAUUUAGAAGUACCGGUAUUGGCCAGGAACAUCCCCGGGAAUGCUGCCGUGGUGAAGCAUGAAGUCACAGGGCUACUGUUUUCCAAUCCUCAGGAGUUUGUUCAUCUGGCAAAGAGACUGGUUAGUGAUCCUGCAUUAGAAAAGGAAAUCGUAGUGAACGGAAGGGAAUACGUGAGAAUGUAUCAUUCAUGGCAGGUGGAAAGAGACACCUACCAACAGCUCAUCAGGAAGCUGGAAGGAAGCACUGAAGAUUGAGGGCCCCGCCUCAUCAGACACCUGCUCUCUGACACACAGCUCUGGGUGCACACUCAGAGACAGAGUUCUGGAUCACGUGGGCCCAGUGCAGUUCAAAUAAAACCAGCCUCAGCGGAAUCCUAGAAAAUGUUAGUCGUGAGUCCCCAGAGCCACUGCAUUCAUCCCAUAUCCUUCUGUGCGUUCAGAUGCUGUCCCAGGCGUGUUCACCAGCCAGUCCUGAUGGAGGUGCAUGAGUGACUGGGUUGACUGGGACAGGGAAAGGGGAACUGGUUUUCAGGGAAUUUGGGAGAGAAUUUGAUUACCUGCCUUAGGGCUUUGGUGUGGACAAUAGAGGCUUAUUUUCAAGCAGUCAUGGUUCAGACUCCUCCCGCCUGCCUUCUGACCAACCUCUCCCCAUCGUUGCCAGUUUGAAAGGCAAAAGCAAAACAGACGUGUCAGCUGAGCCGAGUCCUCGCAGGAUUUUUGUUGUGAUCUCAGGACUCUGACAGGCACGUGGGUGACCCGAGGCUUCUCUGAACACUAGAAAGCGCUGUGAGUGAGCUCACGCCCGGCACAGCUCACUUUUCAAUGGUGGAAUUGAAAGUUGUGCUUUUUAGAAAAGUGGCCAGGCUGCCCGCAGGCCCCGCCCACCUCUUGGCUGAAUUUGAGUGGAAAACCAGGAAGGAACAAGCGCCACGUCACGCAUAGCCUGCAAAUCGCCCGCGUGACCCUGAGAUGGAGGCCUGAGGCUUUGGGUCCAGGGUGGGCUCUUCCCCUUCCCACAUCAGGGACCCGGGGAUGGAUGUCGGAAGGGUCACCAGCCUCCAGCCUUUGGCAGGAUGGAGCUUGGGUCUGCAGGGCUUUGCAGCCACACAGCGAGGUCAGUCCGGGGCCAGCCGCGCCAUCAUGGUAAUGGUGGCCUCGCCCCAUCCAUGUCAUCCAUGUCACAUGAGGACGUGCAGUCUUCCUUGUCCUCUCCUAGUGGAAUUUGCCUGGGAGAACCUCCACUGAAUACUGAAAUUGUUGCAUGCCUGUGGAUUCCUUACGACAAUGGGGAACGCGGUGUUUCCCACCUCUUGUGGGUAGAAAGCAGUCUGCUUUGAGGAGGCGAGAAGGCAAAGCCAGGGCAGGGCGUUGCUGUGGGAAGCGUUCGGUGAAAGCGGGUUUCGACGCUUAGGAGGGCCGAGGGAGAAGAUUCCACCAGCAUUGUCCUUGCUUCAAGUUUUAGGAUGUCUGAACUUUCAGCUUUCAUGUUUUCAACCAUCAUUUUUUUAAUGGCACAACCUACAUCUUGUUUUUAAAAGAAGUAGCCUCAAAUUAAACUCCUUAAACUCUGAUGCCCUGGGGAUGAGAACAACUAGCUUGGAUCUCGUGCCGUGUAAUUCAAUGUUUCAUUCCGCUGCCUCCAUCAUGUAAUAGAAUCGCUUUCCAGAAAGGCAGUUAACUGGAAGCAGCAGAGGCUCCCAGCCGUGAGAGGACUGCUCAACAAUGCCCCCCAUCGCCGCCCCCCCACCCCUCGCACCCCUUGUGUUUUCCCUCUGAGGGGCCCAAGGGUUAUGGCUUUCAUGUCUAGGUGUGGGGACAGAGGAGGGAGAGGCAGAUCCUGGGCCGGGAGAGGAUGGCCUGGUCUGAAUCUGGAGUAAUUAAUGCCACCCAAAGAAAAGGCCCUGCCAGGUCCAAUGUUGUCUUAGAUCUGAUGAUGCUGCUAUUUACAAAACACUGAUCGUCCGAAAGCUUGAAUCUGUUCCUCCUCGAAUGACCCUGUAGAUGCCUGACCUCCACCGUACCUCCACAUCACUAUUCAUGUCCUUCUAGGAAAAUGUGCACAUGCCUCACGCACUAUGUGGGAAGGGCGUGUUUUUAAAUUAAUAAAGUGUGUCACCAUUAGCCAUACGAAAA